AACAUUUCACAUCCAGAGUUCAUUUUGGUGUGCAGUAACCUUAAAAGUUAAGAGGGUAUCAAGAACAGUUGAUGAUUCAGAACUUGGUAAGUUAUGGGAUUAAGUAGUAUAUGAAGCCCAUCUAUGUUUUAAAAAUUAGGAUUUGCUCUUCACUGAAGGUGAAUUUCCUGACUCUUUUCUAAGAGUCAUAUUCAACUACAUUAAUAACUGCUGGUAAGAGACAGAAAAUAAAAUUAUUUUGAAAUGGAGCUCAGAGAUUUCUAGACGAGAAAUUUAUUUUAAAAUGCUAAUAGAAAAUAAAUUAUAUGGAUAUAUAUUUAUAACACUGAUUUUUAACAGAUGCUCUUAAAAUAACUUUAACCUAGUUUCUUGCUUUGUGAAGACAAAGUUGUUUGUUGUUUCUUUUUUGUUUAACAAAGGUAACUUCAUGAGUAUUUGACAGUAUAUUUCUUUUGGCUCAUAUUUCUGUGUAUUCACCUGCUUGUAAAUCAUAGCAAAAAGGAACAAGCUAAUGGACUAAUAUAUGAAGUAAAAGGGCAGAAAAAUGAGCACAUUUACUAUUUAUGCACUGUGUUCUACUGUGUGCUUUCCUCCAGUGCUUACUUAUCCUGAAUUCCUGAACAAUUUUUUCCCUCAUUGUUCAUUAGUGUCAGUCGGUAUGUUAUAGAAAUGUGUGAAUUUCUAUAAAUUAGUUGUGAGUGUGAAUUUCCCACUGUUGGAUUCCUCAGCAGACACCCAAACUUAAUUUUUAUUUCAUGAACUAAAAGUUGUAGCUAAGGCAUGACAUCUGAUCAAAAUUAACACUAUUAUCCUUUGCAAUGAAAAGGGUGAAUAAAACUAAAGUUCCUGGUAGUUGCCCCUGAUACAAGUGUUUGCUUAGCUUUGACCAUACAUCUAUCUAUUUAUUUUACAUUUUACACAUCCAUGGGUAUUCCUCCCGAUAAUGCCAAGGAAUGCUUUCCUUUGCAGGCAUCAUUCUAACAACACAAACACAUUCACUGUGAAUUUUAAACUCUCGUUCUCUUUUUUCCUCCUUUAAUAAAUUAUCUCAUUGAGAUUAUUCAUUGUUUUGGCAGUACUCUAAACGAUCUUGCUUUUGCAAAAUCAUUGUAUAUUCUGUUUAAUGGCAUGUUACUUUAAAACUGUAAAGUUUAGGGUUGCUAAAGGCAAAAGCUGACAAUAUUUGUUAAUAUUGAGAAUAGGUAAAAAUGGGCCUUUGGGCAGUCAACAAAAGUAAAAUUAAAAUCUGACUUUAAAUCUUUUGAAAAUCUAAAAUUAAUAUGGAUUUCUUUAUACCAAUCAGAAAUUCAAAUUUUGUUUUAUGUUACUGAUCUUUAAGUUGUUUAUGUGUCACAGUGAGAGUGGUAGGAACCUUUUUUUUAAUUGUAUGAAGUAAAUGGAAGGAAAAAUAACAGUAUACAUCACUGUGGUAAAACUAUCUUUAAUGAUAGCAUGUUACUUUGGACUACGUUUUGUUUUAUUUUACAGUGAAUUAGGAAGUGUUUUUCAUUGUGUUUUUUGGAAUUCUGGUAAAUGUGAGCAGCAAUUCAUAUGCAUAUAGGUGUAAAAAAGACGUAUUUGAAAAGAUAUGCUGCGUGAAUUUGUCCAGUGAGGAUAAGUAGCAAGUUGUAAUUACCUUCUGUAGUUUAAGUCAUUGGCUGUAUUGAAUACUUCAGUGAAGUAUCGCGGGGGAAAACUGUGGUUGUACAUACUACCUUGUGAGUGUUGCAGGAUUUAGUAGUUCUCAAUGACCAUUGUUACUUUUAAAAAGGAAAAAAAGUAGUGAGGGGAUAGGAUAGGAAGUUUUGAUGUGUGGGAGGGGAAAGGAAUCAUUACUUCUCAGCUGCUGAAGUCGCAGUUUAUUUUGUUUUAGGCCUCUUUGCAUAGCAUAUUCUAGAGGAUGGCGAAGGAUAAUACUUCGGGGUGAAAAUGUUAGUAUCCUUAACAUACUUCCGGGUGGUUUAACUAUUAAUCAGAAGCACCAUGGAGAUUAAAGAAUUGGAGCUAGGGAUUAGAUAGGUUUUAGUGAGGCUUUGCCACGGAAAAGCUAUGAAAUGGGUGAGUCAUUCAACAUCUCCUUGCUUCAGUAUCAGCGUUACUUCGAAAGUGAGGUUUUACUUUCAAAUGUAUUGAGUAUCAGGGUGAAUAGAACUUAGGGCUGAGAGGAUGUCCCUUAUGAUUUUUUGAGCUUGGCAUUUAAUAUUUUACAGCAAAGUUUUUAGCUUAACAUAAUUGAACUUGUACUAGAUAGGGUUAAUAGGCUAGAACAAAAGGUCAAAGCAUAAGGCAUUAGGCUUAAUUAAGGGAGAGCAGGAGUGGCAGGAGUGUGUGACAGUUAAAUGGGUUUCCCACAGACUAAUGUCGGUUACAGUGCAACCAUGCCUCAACUUAAGUGGGUUAUUUUGUGCAAAGGGCAGCAGUGAUUAGCAGUUUGACAUGCCAGACACUUCUGGCCAAUCCCAUCUGUUUUAGAGGUUAAAAAAGCACACCUUUAUGAGCUGAUGGAUUGAUUUGUGUGCCCGUCUGGUAAAGAUUAGAAGUCCAAGGCCAAUGCAGUAAAUGUCAGUUAUAGAGUAUUAUACUUUCUUGGUUGGCUCAUUGUUUUAACCGUCAACUGUUUUAUAAUGGGGGAUAAGUGCUGUUUAUGGUGUUGAAUGCAAGAUAGGUGGGGGAACAGGUGAGGGAGGAAGAAAAAUAUUUCCUAGAUGGACUUGUGAAUCAAAAUAUUCUGUAGCAGGUGUUCACAUUUUAAAUGGAGUGUUUUUGACCUGUUCCUUACAGUUUCAGUCACAUUGUUCUUUUCUGAGUGUUAUCUGAGCAACACUGCCAGUCCAGGAUUUAAUUUUGCAUACAGAAUUGGUAGGUUUGUUUAUUUAGGUACCUCUUUUUAAAGGUGUAAUAAUUUUUUAUUGACCACCUGAACAAGGGAAAAUAAAAUGAAAAUGACACACACACGCGCACACACACACAGAGUUCUGUGUUCUUUUAUGUGGUCAGUCAGGUGCAUGUGAAAAGGAGACCCAGGAGGGGCUCAGGAAAACAAAGUUUAUUAUACUCAUGAGUUCUCGGAGGCACAGCAUGCCAUUCAGGGCCACAUGAGAAAGCCCCAGUGUUGGUCUAGGGGCCAAAGGGGCAGGAGCUAGAAGAGAGACCGGGCUGCAGCCGUUUCUGGAGUAUCUGUGGGAAAGGCAAGGCAGGGCGGGUAACCAAGUUUAGGAUUCGCUAGUUUGCAUUAGCUGUAGGUAAAUGCUACUGCUACUACUACUAAUAAGCUAUAGGUGUGUAAUAAUAGUAGCUUUGAAUAAGUUAUAGGUAUACAGGCUCUAAACUGUAAGAGUGAUCCCUAGUUUGCCUGGUAGAUACCAGGCAGGGGAAUAUUGCCUCCUGGGUGUAUGGGUCAGGUAGAGGAGGUAUCGCUGUGGAUUGUUUAGUUUGCAUGUGAAAGGCACGCUGAGUCCUUUGCCUUCUCUAAGCGUUGGCUGGCCCCUAGAGGGGCAAUCUCUUCCCAGCCAGAAAGGAGUCAAAACCAUCAUAAUAUACAGAAAAUAAGAAACAUAAACAAUACACACAUAUGUACUUGCUUUAAGGGUAGGAUUUACUGUGGUCACGUGAGUUUGAAGUGUGUUUGAACUUAGACUCUAACCUAUUUCUUUCUUCAUUGAAAGUUGUUAAGUGCGAUGCCAUUAGUAUAGUUCAUUUUCAGUUCUGGAUUGUAGCUCAUUUAAAGAUACACAAAUACUACGUUUUGGUUAUAGAAAUUGGCUCCAACAUAUUCUGAAAUUCAAGGAAAGGGAAGAUCCCAAUAUUAUGUGUAUGAAAUCUUCAGACAUUGUCCUCAUAAUCAGUGAACUUAGUAACAUAAAGCAUUGAUUGAUUCUUUUGGGAUAGGCAGAGAGAGAAUGUUUGAGAAAAACAAAAGUUAUCUUAACAGAUUAUAUUCUUCCUGAGGUUUGAGUUUAAGUAGAAAUGUAGCCAAGAACAUUGGAAACACAUUGGAAGGUUCUGAUUGGUCUCAAUAGCUUAUCCUUGUCAAAGAAUAGGAACCAAAUAUUGCCUGUUACCUAGUUACACACAUAUAUUUCAUGUCUGACUCUGAAUUGUUUCUUAUAGAAAGAAAAUUAAAAUACCAAGAUGUGGUCACUGAAAGUUAUAUGUAGAUAACAAUAGGAAUUAGUAUUUUAUUAUGUAUAUGUAUGCAUUUAUUUUAAAACUAAGCUAAUCCAAAGUGAAUUGGCUUAACUUAUAAGAAGACAUUGAGAAAUUUUAUUUCUCAUUUACAAAGGACAAAGUGACAUCAUGUAUUGAAGUUUUUUAGGAAUAUAUUAAUUAAAUAUAUGUCCAUCUGUGUGUUCUUUGUGGAGUAGCAUCUCUUGAAAUGAUUUGGAUCUAAUAUAGAUUUACGUAAGAAAAGUUUUGCCCUUCUCUAUAGGGAGAGAAAAUGAAGAAGCAUGAAUUUUAUAAUAUCAUAGCUUUUUUUUCAUUAAAUCAUUUGUAAGUUGCAAAAGAUUGGCUUGAGUAGUGUAAAAGUGCUUGGAUAGUAAAUUAAAUGUGAGAGAUUUACCUAAUUUAAUGUGUGGAAACUGUUUAAAUGAAUCUUUUGGUGAUGUUGUAUUAAACCUGAAACAAAUACUUCACAGUCUGCAUAUGUACUAAUAUUAUAAACAUUUAAAAAGUACCCUAAAUCCUAUUCUUUUGAGUUCCUUCUCUUUUCUCCAGUAACUUCAAGUGCCAAUAAUACCUUGUUUGUGUUACAAUUGCAUUUUACAAAGCUAAAGGGAAAUAAUUUGUAGGGUUAACUUUUGUGUGUGUGUGUUUUGAUAUACUCUUGAGGUUUUGGAGAAUACACAUUAUCCCCUGUAAUCUAUGAUUGUUAAUCUGUCAAUCUAUUGUACCUCUUUUCUUUUAUUAAUAUAGUAUUAUUGGAUUUGAGACAUGUAAACUAUGCUUCUCUAAGCAAAUUAGUUGAAUAUAUUCGUGUUUAGGUUAUAAAAAAUGAAAGCAAGAACUCUUAACAUACUUGGCAUCCUGUGUUUUAAAUUCUUUUCCUAAAACUAUAGCUUUGUAACCUGAAUAUUAGGUGUUAGAAAUUUUAUAAGACAAUGGGAAAAUAAUGGCCCUAUAUUGUAUUUUGCUUCUAAAUGCUAUUAGGGUAUAGAAUUGUUCUUUAUUUAGGCAGAUUAAUUUUAAGAAGAAAGCCAUAAUAUAUGAUGGACUUAUUCAAAUAUAUAUUUUAGUGUUAUUUAUAUAUUUGUAAAAUGAAUACGUGUGUGUGUGUAUGUAUUUGUAUGAUAUAUUUUAAAUGGAGAUGUCUACACCUGUUGAUUGCAUUAAGCAUUUAGUAUCCCCUAAUGAAGGAUGGAAAAGGUGCUGCCACACUGUCUAAGUGGAUCAUUUCUCCUUGGUAAAUUACACACAUUCUACUUUUUUGUAUUCUGUGACCUUGCGGUCAGUGACUUCAGCCCAGAAUAGUUUCAGAGUCAUGUAAAUGAAUGCAAUUAAGGUAUUGCCUAUCAUCUUACAUAGUUCAGAUGGAACCUUAUUGGAUAGAGAGGUUUAUUUGCUUUAUGAGAAAGGUCAAAAUAAGGUUAAAUUUUAUUACAUAAAAUGAUUUGGUAAUGUUUUUAUUUAGCUCCUAAAAAAGUAAUGUCCUAAUAGGAAAUGAUAAUGCUUUUUGUUUUUCCUUUAUCACCUGGAGGUCUCUUCAGGUUCUGUUUGUUUUUGUCUGAUUAUAAACUCUAUUUUGAGGAGAUGCCUUCUGUCGACUAAGAUUUUGGGAACAUCCUGCCUGUAGUUAAGAUUCUAGAUAUCUUUGACUUAUACACUUAGGUGACAUACCCUGUUAAUGAUGUAGGGUAGCUUUGGUGUUGCUGAUGUGUAGGCAUACUUCAUUUUAUUGUGCUUCACUUUACUGCUCUUUGAAGAUAAUUUUGUUUUUUACAAACUGAAGGUUUGUGGCAGCCCUGCAUUGAGCAAGUACCAUUUUUUCAACAGCAUGUUUUCAGUUUGUGUCUUUGUGGUCAUGUUUUGAUAAUUCUCACAAUAUAUAAAACUUUUUCAUAUUAUUAUAUGUGUCAUGGUGAUCUGUAAUCAGUGAUCUUUGAUGUUACUAUUGUGAUUGUUUUGAGGUACCAUGAACUGUGCCCAUAUCAGCCGGCGAACUUGUUCAGUGUGGUCUGACUGCUUUACAGACUGGCUGUUCCCCCAUCUCAUCUCCCUUUCCUUGGGAUUCCCUGUUCCUUGAGACACAACAAUAUUGAAAUUAGGCCAAUUAAUAACCCUAUAAUGGCUAAGUAUUUAAAUGCAAGGAAAAGUUGUAGGUCUCUUACUUUAAAUCAAGAGCUAGAAAAGGUUAAGCUCAGUGAGGAAGGCAUGUCAAAAGCCAAGCUCUUCUGAAAGCUAGGCCUCUUGUGCCAGUUCACCAAGUUGUGAAUGUAAAAGGAAAAGUUCUUAAAGGACAUUAAAAGUGCUACUCCAGUGAACACAUGAAUGAUAAGAACACAAAGCAGCCUGAUAUGGUUUGGCUGUGUCUCCACCCAAAUCUCAUCUUGAAUUGUAGUUCCUAUACUCCCCAUGUGUCCUGGGAGGGACCCAGUGGGAGGUAAUUGAAUCAUGGAGGCAGUUACCCCCAUGCUGUUCUCGUGAUAGUGAGUUCUCAUGAGAUCUGAUGGUUUUUUAAUUUAAUUUUAAUGAUUUAUUUAUUUCUGAGAAGAAGUCUCGCUCUGCCGCCCAGGCUGGAGUGCAGUGGCGCGGUCUCAGCUCACUGCAAGCUCCGCCUCCUGGGUUCACGCCAUUCUCCCGCCUCAGCCUCCCAAGUAGCUGGGACCACAGGCGCCCGCCACCACGCCUGGCUAAUUUUUUGAUUUUUAGUAGAGAUGGGGUUUCACCAUGUUAGCCAGGAUGGUCUCUGUCUCCUGACCUCGUGAUCUGCCUGCCUCGGCCUCCCAAAGUGCUGGAAUUACAGGCGUGAGCCACCGCGCCCGGCCGAGAUCUGAUGGUUUUAUAAGAGGCUUUUCCCACUUUGCUUGGCACUUCUUCCUGCUGCCUUGUGAAGAAGGUGCCUUGCUUUCCCCUCACCUUCUGCCAUGAUUUUAAGUUUCCUGAGACCUCCCCAACAAUGCGGAACUCUGAGUCAAUGAAACCUCUUUCCUUUAUAAAUUACCCAGUCUCGGGCAUUUUUUCAUAGCUGUGUGAGAACGGACUAAUAGACAGCCUUAUUGCUAAUAUGGAGAAUAUUUUAGUAGUCUGCCUAGAAAAUCAAAGCAGCCAUAACAUUCCCUUAAGCCAAAACCUAAUCCAGAGCAGCGCCUCACUCUAAUUCCACAAAGGCCGAGAGGAGAUGAAGAAACUGCAGAAGAAAAGUUGGAAGCUAGCAGAGGUUUGUUCAUGAAGUUUAAGGAUAGAAGCUGCCUGGAUAACAUAAAAGUGCACGAUGAAGCAGGUAAUGCUGAUGUAGAAGCUACAGCAAGCUUCCAGAAGAUCUAGGUAAGAUCAUUGAUGAAGAUGGCUACAUUAAACAGCAGAUUUUCAGUGUAAAUGAAACAGCCUUCUGUUGGAUGAAUAUGCCAUCUAGGACUUUAAUAGCUAGAGAGGAGAAACCAAUGCCUGGCCUCAGAACCUCAAAGGACAAACUGACUUUCUUGUUAGUGGAUAAUACAGCUGGUGACUUGAAGUGGAAACCAAUGUUUGGCCAUUCCAAAAAUCCUAAGCCCCUUAAGAAUUAUACUAAAUCUCUUCUACCUAUGCUGUAUAAAUGGAAGAAGAAGCCUGGAUGACAGAACAUCUGUUUACAGCAUGGUUUGCUGAAUAUUUUAGGCCCCCUCUUGAGACCAACUGCUCAGAAAAAAAAGAUUCCUAUCGAAAUAUUACUGUUUAUUGACCACGCACCUGGUCACUCAAGAGCUCUGAUGGAGAUGUACAAGGAAGUUAAUGUUAAUUUUCAUGGCUGCUAAUACAACAUCUAUUCUGUAGCCUGUGGAUCAAGGAGUAAUUUCAACUUUCAAGUCUUACUAUUGAAGAAAUACAUCUUGUGAAGCUGUAGUUGCCAUAGAUAGUGAUUCCUCUGAUGGAUCUGGGCAAAGGCAAUUGUAAACCUUCUGAAAAGGAUUCACCAUUCUAGAUGCCAUUGAGAACAUUUGUGAUUAAUGGGAGGAGGUCAAAAUACUAACAUUAAUAGGAGUUUGAAAGAAGCUGCUUCCACCCCUUAUGGAUAACUUUGGCGGGUUGAAGACAUCAGUGGAGGAAGUAACUGCAGAUGUGGUGGAAAUUGCAAGAAAACUAGAAUUAGAAGUGGAGCCUGAAGAUGUGACUGAAUUUGUAUAAUCUCAUGAGAAAACAUGGACGGAUGAGGAGUUACUCCUUAUAGAUGAGCAAAGAAAGUAGUUACUAGAGAUGGAAUCUACUCCUGAUUGAAGAUACUGUGAACAUUGUUGAAAUAACAACGAAGGAUUUAGAAUAUCAUGUAAACAUAAUUGAUAAAACAGUGGCAGGGUUUGAGAGGAUUGACUCCCAUCUAGAAAGAUAUUCUACUGUGGGUAAAAUGCUAUCAAACAGCAUUACAUGCUACAGAGAAUUAUUCUGUGAAAGGAAGAAUCAGCCGAUGUGGCAAACUUCAUUGUUGUCUUGUUUUAAGAAAUCAUUACAGAGACCCCAACCUUCAGCAACCACAAGCCUGAUCAUUUGGCAGCCAUCAAUAUGGAGGCAAGGUGCCCACCACUGAAGAGUAAAACUCUCUAAAGAUUCACAUGAUUGUUAGCAUUUUUAGCAAUAAAGUAUUUUUAUACUAAGGUAUGUACAUUGUUUCGACAUAAAGCUUUUGCACACUUAAUAGACUAUAGUACAGUGUAAACAUAACUUUUAUGUGCACUAGGAAACCAAAAAACUUGUGUGACUUGCUUUAUUGUGAUAUUUGCUUUAUUUUAGUGAUCUGGAAUGGAACCCACUAUAUCUCUGAGGAAGUGUUUGGAUUGUGAGCUAUUUCAGAACUGUUCUCAGGACUCAUUAUUUUAACAUUUGGGAGAAACACAGCCAGAAGAACACUGAUAUUUGCAUUUAAUGGGGAACAAAAGAUGAAGAAGGAAAAGGAAUAUAUUCACUAAGGAUUCUAUCUGCUUACUGCUACAGACCUAUGUGUUAAGGAAUUCUUCUCCUCCUCCUUGCGUAGAAGUUGAUCAGCACUGUGGUCAGACUGCAUUUAUCUUGUCAUUGCCAGAAGAAAUCUUGGACAGAAUGUAACAGUACGUCUCUCUCUGAUUGCGAUGGAAGGUGAUAAACUGAUACUCCUUUAUUAAAGUUACAUCGCACUCACCACAGAAAACCAUUCUUUAAAGUGAAUAGAAACCAAGCCCUUGUGAACACUUCUAUUGAACAUGACUCAUGGAGAAGAGCUUGGCUCUGAUGUGCACCAGGAUUCUAUUGUUUUAACUUACCUAGAAGGAUUACUAAUGCAUCAGGCAGCAGGGGGAUCAGGUACUGCCGUUGACAAAAAGUCUGCUGGGCAUAAUGAAGAGGAUCAGAACUUUAACAUUUCUGGCAGUGCAUUUCCCACCUGUCAAAGUAAUGGUCCAGUUCUCAAUACACAUACAUAUCAGGGGUCUGGCAUGCUGCACCUCAAAAAAGCCAGACUGUUGCAGUCUUCUGAGGACUGGAAUGCAGCAAAGCGGAAGAGGCUGUCUGAUUCUAUCAUGAAUUUAAACGUAAAGAAGGAAGCUUUGCUAGCUGGCAUGGUUGACAGUGUGCCUAAAGGCAAACAGGAUAGCACAUUACUGGCCUCUUUGCUUCAGUCAUUCAGCUCUAGGCUGCAGACUGUUGCUCUGUCACAACAAAUCAGGCAGAGCCUCAAGGAGCAAGGAUAUGCCCUCAGUCAUGAUUCUUUAAAAGUGGAGAAGGAUUUAAGGUGCUAUGGUGUUGCAUCAAGUCACUUAAAAACUUUGUUGAAGAAAAGUAAAGUUAAAGAUCAAAAGCCUGAUACGAAUCUUCCUGAUGUGACUAAAAACCUCAUCAGAGAUAGGUUUGCAGAGUCUCCUCAUCAUGUUGGACAAAGUGGAACAAAGGUCAUGAGUGAACCGUUGUCAUGUGCUGCAAGAUUACAGGCUGUUGCAAGCAUGGUGGAAAAAAGGGCUAGUCCUGCCACCUCACCUAAACCUAGUGUUGCUUGUAGCCAGUUAGCAUUACUUCUGUCAAGCGAAGCCCAUUUGCAGCAGUAUUCUCGAGAACACGCUUUAAAAACGCAAAAUGCAAAUCAAGCAGCAAGUGAAAGACUUGCUGCUAUGGCCAGAUUGCAAGAAAAUGGCCAGAAGGAUGUUGGCAGUUACCAGCUCCCAAAAGGAAUGUCAAGCCAUCUUAAUGGUCAGGCAAGAACAUCAUCAAGCAAACUGAUGGCUAGCAAAAGUAGUGCUACAGUGUUUCAAAAUCCAAUGGGUAUCAUUCCUUCUUCCCCUAAAAAUGCAGGUUAUAAGAACUCACUGGAAAGAAACAAUAUAAAACAAGCUGCUAACAAUAGUUUGCUUUUACAUCUUCUUAAAAGCCAGACUAUACCUAAGCCAAUGAAUGGACACAGUCACAGUGAGAGAGGAAGCAUUUUUGAGGAAAGUAGUACACCUACAACUAUUGAUGAAUAUUCAGAUAACAAUCCUAGUUUUACAGAUGACAGCAGUGGUGAUGAAAGUUCUUAUUCCAACUGUGUUCCCAUAGACUUGUCUUGCAAACACCGAACUGAAAAAUCAGAAUCUGACCAACCUGUUUCCCUGGAUAACUUCACUCAAUCCUUGCUAAACACUUGGGAUCCAAAAGUCCCAGAUGUAGAUAUCAAAGAAGAUCAAGAUACCUCAAAGAAUUCUAAGCUAAACUCACACCAGAAAGUAACACUUCUUCAAUUGCUACUUGGCCAUAAGAAUGAAGAAAAUGUAGAAAAAAACACCAGCCCUCAGGGAGUACACAAUGAUGUGAGCAAGUUCAAUACACAAAAUUAUGCAAGGACUUCUGUGAUAGAAAGCCCCAGUACAAAUCGGACUACUCCAGUGAGCACUCCACCUUUACUUACAUCAAGCAAAGCAGGGUCUCCCAUCAAUCUCUCUCAACACUCUCUGGUCAUCAAAUGGAAUUCCCCACCAUAUGUCUGCAGUACUCAGUCUGAAAAGCUAACAAAUACUGCAUCUAACCACUCAAUGGACCUUACAAAAAGCAAAGACCCACCAGGAGAGAAACCAGCCCAAAAUGAAGGUGCACAGAACUCUGCAACGUUUAGUGCCAGUAAGCUGUUACAAAAUUUAGCACAAUGUGGAAUGCAGUCAUCCAUGUCAGUGGAAGAGCAGAGACCCAGCAAACAGCUGUUAACUGGAAACACAGAUAAACCGAUAGGUAUGAUUGAUAGAUUAAAUAGCCCUUUGCUCUCAAAUAAAACAAAUGCAGUUGAAGAAAAUAAAGCAUUUAGUAGUCAACCAACAGGUCCUGAACCAGGGCUUUCUGGUUCUGAAAUAGAAAAUCUGCUUGAAAGACGUACUGUCCUCCAGUUGCUCCUGGGGAACCCCAACAAAGGGAAGAGUGAAAAAAAAGAGAAAACUCCCUUAAGAGAUGAAAGUACUCAGGAACACUCAGAGAGAGCUUUAAGUGAACAAAUACUGAUGGUGAAAAUAAAAUCUGAGCCUUGUGAUGACUUACAAAUUCCUAACACAAAUGUGCACUUGAGCCAUGAUGCUAAGAGUGCCCCAUUCUUGGGUAUGGCUCCUGCUGUGCAGAGAAGCGCACCUGCCUUACCAGUGUCCGAAGACUUUAAAUCGGAGCCUGUUUCACCUCAGGAUUUUUCUUUCUCCAAGAAUGGUCUGCUAAGUCGAUUGCUAAGACAAAAUCAAGAUAGUUACCUGGCAGAUGAUUCAGACAGGAGUCACAGAAAUAAUGAAAUGGCACUUCUAGAAUCAAAGAAUCUUUGCAUGGUCCCUAAGAAAAGGAAGCUUUAUACUGAGCCAUUAGAAAAUCCAUUUAAAAAGAUGAAAAACAACAUUGUUGAUGCUGCAAACAAUCACAGUGCCCCAGAAGUACUGUAUGGGUCCUUGCUUAACCAGGAAGAGCUGAAAUUUAGCAGAAAUGAUCUUGAAUUUAAAUAUCCUGCUGGUCAUGGCUCAGCCAGCGAAAGUGAACACAGGAGUUGGGCCAGAGAGAGCAAAAGCUUUAAUGUUCUGAAACAGCUGCUUCUCUCAGAAAACUGUGUGCGAGAUUUGUCCCCGCACAGAAGUAACUCUGUGGCUGACAGUAAAAAGAAAGGACACAAAAAUAAUGUGACCAACAGCAAACCUGAAUUUAGCAUUUCUUCUUUAAAUGGACUGAUGUACAGUUCCACUCAGCCCAGCAGUUGCAUGGAUAACAGGACAUUUUCAUACCCAGGUGUAGUAAAAACUCCUGUGAGUCCUACUUUCCCUGAGCACUUGGGCUGUGCAGGGUCUAGACCAGAAUCUGGGCUUUUGAAUGGGUGUUCCAUGCCCAGUGAGAAAGGACCCAUUAAGUGGGUUAUCACUGAUGCGGAGAAGAAUGAGUAUGAAAAAGACUCUCCAAGAUUGACCAAAACCAACCCAAUACUAUAUUACAUGCUUCAAAAAGGAGGCAAUUCUGUUACCAGUCGAGAAACACAAGACAAGGACAUUUGGAGGGAGGCUUCAUCUGCUGAAAGUGUCUCACAGGUCACAGCCAAAGAAGAGUUACUUCCUACUGCAGAAACGAAAGCUUCUUUCUUUAAUUUAAGAAGCCCUUACAAUAGCCAUAUGGGAAAUAAUGCUUCUCGCCCACACAGCGCAAAUGGAGAAGUUUAUGGACUUCUGGGAAGCGUGCUAACGAUAAAGAAAGAAUCAGAAUAAAAUGUACCUGCCAUCCAGUUUUGGAUCUUUUUAAAACUAAUGAGUAUGAACUUGAGAUCUGUAUAAAUAAGAGCAUGAUUUGAAAAAAAGCAUGGUAUAAUUGAAACUUUUUUCAUUUUGAAAAGUAUUGGUUACUGGUGAUGUUGAAAUAUGCAUACUAAUUUUUGCUUAACAUUAGAUGUCAUGAGGAAACUACUGAACUAGCAAUUGGUUGUUUAACACUUCUGUAUGCAUCAGAUAACAACUGUGAGUAGCCUAUGAAUGAAAUUCUUUUAUAAAUAUUAGGCAUAAAUUAAAAUGUAAAACUCCAUUCAUAGUGGAUUAAUGCAUUUUGCUGCCUUUAUUAGGGUACUUUAUUUUGCUUUUCAGAAGUCAGCCUACAUAACACAUUUUUAAAGUCUAAACUGUUAAACAACUCUUUAAAGGAUAAUUAUCCAAUAAAAAAAAACCUAGUGCUGAUUCACAGCUUAUUAUCCAAUUCAAAAAUAAAUUAGAAAAAUAUAUGCUUACAUUUUUCACUUUUGCUAAAAAGAAAAAAAAAAGGUGUUUAUUUUUAACUCUUGGAAGAGGUUUUGUGGUUCCCAAUGUGUCUGUCCCACCCUGAUCCUUUUCAAUAUAUAUUUCUUUAAACCUUGUGCUACUUAGUAAAAAUUGAUUACAAUUGAGGGAAGUUUGAUAGAUCCUUUAAAAAAAAGGCAGAUUUCCAUUUUUUGUAUUUUAACUACUUUACUAAAUUAAUACUCCUCCUUUUACAGAAUUAGAAAAGUUAACAUUUAUCUUUAGGUGGUUUCCUGAAAAGUUGAAUAUUUAAGAAAUUGUUUUUAACAGAAGCAAAAUGGCUUUUCUUUGGACAGUUUUCACCAUCUCUUGUAAAAGUUAAUUCUCACCAUUCCUGUGGUACCUGCGAGUGUUAUGACCAGGAUUCCUUAAACCUGAACUCAGACCACUUGCAUUAGAACCAUCUGGAGCACUUGUUUUAAAAUGCAGAUUCAUAGGCAGCAUCUCAGAUCUACAGAACAAGAAUCUCUGCUAAGUGGACCUGGAAUCUUCCAUCUGCAUCUUAACAUGCUCUCUAGGUGUUUCUUGUGUUUGAGAACCAUGACUUAUGACUUUCCUCAGAACAUGAGACUGUAAAACAAAAACAAAAAACUAUGUGAUGCCUCUAUUUUCCCCAAUACAGUCACACAUCAGCUCAAAAUUUGCAAUAUUGUAGUUCAUAUAUUACCGUUAUGUCUUUGGAAAUCGGGUUCAGAACACUUUUUAUGACAAAAAUUGGGUGGAGGGGAUAACUUUCAUAUCUGGCUCAACAUCUCAGGAAAAUCUGUGAUUAUUUGUGUGUUCUAAUGAGUAACAUCUACUUAGUUAGCCUUAGGGAUGGAAAAACAGGGCCACUUACCAAACUCAGGUGAUUCCAGGAUGGUUUGGAAACUUCUCCUGAAUGCAUCCUUAACCUUUAUUAAAACCAUUGUCCUAAGAACAAUGCCAACAAAGCUUACAACAUUUAGUUUAAACCCAAGAAGGGCACUAAACUCAGAUUGACUAAAUAAAAAGUACAAAGGGCACAUAUACGUGACAGAAUUGUACACAAUCACUCCAUUGGAUCUUUUACUUUAAAGUAGUGAUGAAAAGUACAUGUUGAUACUGUCUUAGAAGAAAUUAAUAUAUUAGUGAAGCCACAUGGGGUUUCAGUUGCGAAACAGGUCUGUUUUUAUGUUCAGUUUGUACAAUCCACAAUUCAUUCACCAGAUAUUUUGUUCUUAAUUGUGAACCAGGUUAGCAAAUGACCUAUCAAAAAUUAUUCUAUAAUCACUACUAGUUAGGAUAUUGAUUUAAAAUUGUUCUACUUGAAGUGGUUUCUAAGAUUUUUAUAUUAAAAAUAGGUGUGAUUUCCUAAUAUGAUCUAAAACCCUAAAUGGUUAUUUUUCCUCAGAAUGAUUUGUAAAUAGCUACUGGAAAUAUUAUACAGUAAUAGGAGUGGGUAUUAUGCAACAUCAUGGAGAAGUGAAGGCAUAGGCUUAUUCUGACAUAAAAUUCCACUGGCCAGUUGAAUAUAUUCUAUUCCAUGUCCAUACUAUGACAAUCUUAUUGUCAACACUAUAUAAAUAAGCUUUUAAACAAGUCAUUUUUCUUGAUCGUUGUGGAAGGUUUGGAGCCUUAGAGGUAUGUCAGAAAAAAUAUGUUGGUAUUCUCCCUUGGGUAGGGGGAAAUGACCUUUUUACAAGAGAGUGAAAUUUAGGUCAGGGAAAAGACCAAGGGCCAGCAUUGCUACUUUUGUGUGUGUGUGUGUGGGUUUUGUUUUGUUUUUUUGGUUGGCUGGUUGUUUUCGUUGUUGUUAACAAAGGAAUGAGAAUAUGUAAUACUUAAAUAAACAUGACCACGAAGAAUGCUGUUCUGAUUUACUAGAGAAUGUUCCCAAUUUGAAUUUAGGGUGAUUUUAAAGAACAGUGAGAAAGGGCAUACAUCCACAGAUUCACUUUGUUUAUGCAUAUGUAGAUACAAGGAUGCACAUAUACACAUUUUCAAGGACUAUUUUAGAUAUCUAGACAAUUUCUUCUAAUAAAGUCAUUUGUGAAAGGGUACUACAGCUUAUUGACAUCAGUAAGGUAGCAUUCAUUACCUGUUUAUUCUCUGCUGCAUCUUACAGAAGAGUAAACUGGUGAGAGUAUAUAUUUUAUAUAUAUAUAUAUAUAUAUAUAUAUAAUAUGUAUAUAUAUAUAUAUUGACUUGUUACAUGAAGAUGUUAAAAUCGGUUUUUAAAGGUGAUGUAAAUAGUGAUUUCCUUAAUGAAAAAUACAUAUUUUGUAUUGUUCUAAUGCAACAGAAAAGCCUUUUAAUCUCUUUGGUUCCUGUAUAUUCCAUGUAUAAGUGUAAAUAUAAUCAGACAGGUUUAAAAGUUGUGCAUGUAUGUAUACAGUUGCAAGUCUGGACAAAUGUAUAGAAUAAACCUUUUAUUUAAGUUGUGAUUACCUGCUGCAUGAAAAGUGCAUGGGGGACCCUGUGCAUCUGUGCAUUUGGCAAAAUGUCUUAACAAAUCAGAUCAGAUGUUCAUCCUAACAUGACAGUAUUCCAUUUCUGGACAUGACGUCUGUGGUUUAAGCUUUGUGAAAGAAUGUGCUUUGAUUCGAAGGGUCUUAAAGAAUUUUUUUAAUCGUCAACCACUUUUAAACAUAAAGAAUUCACACAACUACUUUCAUGAAUUUUUUAAUCCCAUUGCAAACAUUAUUCCAAGAGUAUCCCAGUAUUAGCAAUACUGGAAUAUAGGCACAUUACCAUUCAUAGUAAGAAUUCUGGUGUUUACACAACCAAAUUUGAUGCGAUCUGCUCAGUAAUAUAAUUUGCCAUUUUUAUUAGAAAUUUAAUUUCUUCAUGUGAUGUCAUGAAACUGUACAUACUGCAGUGUGAAUUUUUUUGUUUUGUUUUUUAAUCUUUUAGUGUUUACUUCCUGCAGUGAAUUUGAAUAAAUGAGAAAAAAUGCAUUGUC